GCCGCUGCCUCCCGGGCUGGGGCACGAGUGGCUGCGGAGUGUGGGUGGUUGGGCGUGAGGGGCCGACGGGCUCGCGCGCGCGCCGUCUGCUGAGGUCCCUCGGGAAGGAGGAGAGCGCCUGACGCCGACCCGCAGGCGCAGCCCGGCAGUCGGCGGCGCGCCGAGGGCGGAGGUGGUGCGUGCGUGCGUGUGUGUGUGUGUGUGUGUGUGUGUGUGUGUGUGUGUGUGGAGCUCGGGUGCCAAGGGCGAGCCGUCAGUCCCCGGGUGCGAGUCCCUGCUGUCUUCCACACCCUUCCUCCCUCCAGGCUCCUUUCCUACAUCCUUCCCGCGCCCCCACGGUUGCGGACCGAGCGAGAACCCCCUUAAGCAGGUGUGGGGGGCGUGCGGGGUGGCACGAGACAAAAGGGGCACGGGGGUAAGCCCGCCAUGGCCUCCCGGAGCCUGGGGGGCCUGAGCGGGAUCCGCGGCGGUGGCGGCGGAGGCGGCAAGAAAAGCCUGAGCGCCCGCAAUGCUGCGGUGGAGAGGAGGAACCUGAUCACCGUGUGCAGGUACGGCAGCGCAGGGCGAGGGGAACCAGCCUCCCGCCGGGGCUGAGAGCUCUGGGCUUCCGCGCGGGUCCUUGGGGGUCCCGGGCAUGAUGGGCUGCCGCCCAGUGCCCCCGCCUAUGUUGCGCCAGCCAAAUCUGUGAGCGCGCAGCUCCUUGGACAGGGGCCCGGGUCUGGACACCGUCGCAGCCCUGGACUUUGUGUCAGUUCCAGUGCUGAAGGUACUGGAGGGUAGAGCUUGGGGCGGGGCUGGAGGAGGAUUUGUUUUGAAUGUGCAAUCUAGCGUCAGAGUGAAAGAGGAGGGCAAGGAAGAAGAGCUCUUUCAUUUAAUGCCCAUUCAGCUGUCAGCGAGCUUUGGAUAAAGUGGUUUUCUGUGAAGACCCUGAUUGAUCGGUCUUGCUUUGAGACAAUUGAUGAUUCUUCUCCUGAAUUUAACAAUUUUGCAGCUAUUUUGGAACAGAUUUUAAGCCACCGGCUAAAAGGUCAAGUAACCUGGUUUGGUUAUGAAAGUCCUCGUAGCUUCUGGGACUAUAUCAGAGUGGCUUGCCGGAAAGUUUCACAGAAUUGUAUCUGCAGCAUUGAAAAUAUGGAAAAUGUCAGUUCUUCUAGAGCUAAGGGUAGAGCCUGGAUCAGAGUAGCACUCAUGGAAAAACAUUUAUCUGAAUACAUCUCUACAGCUCUGAGAGACUUCAAAACAACCAGGAGAUUUUAUGAAGAUGGAGCAAUUGUCUUGGGUGAAGAAGCAAAUAUGCUUGCUGGCAUGCUUCUAGGACUCAAUGCUAUUGAUUUCAGUUUCUGCCUAAAGGGAGAGGGGCUGGAUGGCAGUUUUCCUGCUGUAAUAGACUAUACACCAUAUUUGAAGUAUAUCCAAAGUUCUGAUAGUAUCAGCAGUGAUGAGGAGGAGCUAAGGACUUUGGGAAGCAGUGGUAGCGAAAGCAGUACUCCAGAGAAUGUCGGACCUCCUUUCCUCAUGGAUGAGAACAGUUGGUUCAACAAGUGUAAGAGAGUUAAACAAAAGUAUCAGCUUACCCUGGAACAGAAGGGUUACCUUGAAGAACUCUUACGACUUCGAGAGAACCAACUAUCUGAAUCUGUCUCCCAGAAUAAAAUACUACUUCAAAGGAUUGAAGAUUCCGAUCUGGCUCAUAAACUGGAGAAGGAACAAUUAGAAUAUAUAAUUGUGGAGCUUCAAGAUCAGCUGACUGUGCUAAAGAAUAAUGAUUUAAGAUCGAGACAAGAGUUAACUGCCCAUCUCACCAACCAGUGGCCUUCUCCAGGAGCUCUGGAUGUCAAUGCUGUUGCCUUGGAUACGUUGCUUUACCGAAAACACAAUAAACAGUGGUAUGAGAAAAGUUAUCAAAGUCUUGACCAGUUAUCAGCAGAAGUUAGCCUUUCUCAGACUUCACUAGAUCCAGGCCAGUCACAAGAAGGAGAUGGAAAACAAGACACAUUAAAUGUAAUGAGUGAAGGUAAGGAAGAUACUCCCUCAUUACUUGGCCUCUGUGGAUCUCUAACGUCAGUGGCAAGUUACAAGUCUCUAACAAGCUUAAAAUCUAAUGACUACCUUGCAAGUCCUACAACAGAGAUGACAAGUCCAGGCCUAACUCCAUCCUGAAAAUUUUUGUGUAAAAGCCAAAACUUUUUAUGUUGUAAAUGUUUAAUUUACAUGUUUGACUGCUGGGAAGACCUUUGAAAUUUUAUAUUGUUCUGGUACAUGUCUGAAAUUCUAUUGCUUGGAGAGAAUCCCCUCCAGAUAAGAGAUUUUGAGUGAAAAACAUAAUGAUCCUGCCAUUUUUCAUUUUUAAAAUUCUUACAUUUGUCAUUGAGAAAGUUCAAAAUGGAAUAGGCUUUAAAAAAAAAAAAACUUUCAAAGAUCCGCCAAAUCAUUCAUAGCAAAUUGUACAUAUUGUUCAGCUGAUUUUUAUAUAUUUAAAUACACCUUAGUGGCCAGAGACUGACUUCAAGGUUUUAUUCCAGAGACUCCAGAGACUUAAGCUAAGUAUUUUUUCAUUCUUUCAGAUUUUCAAAAAAAAAAAAAAAAAAAGUUAAUUUCAUUUUUUCAUUAAUGUCUUCCUAAGUUCUAUGCUUUAAAUGCCUUGUUUUUAAUAACGGGAAAGUUCUCAGCUGCAUUUUCACAGUGGCUUAUUCAGUUUUUCUUUAAUAUUUACCAUUUGGUAUCAAUUCAGCAUUCCACUUAACAUUUUAUAAAUUCCAUAGGAACAUGCCUGUUUUGGUAGUUACUGACUUAAUUUGUUAGUGCCACAAGGAAAAUAUUUUACAGUAUUUUAUGCCAUUUAGGCAAAAUGAAUAAACUGUUUUCCAAGAUUUUCUUAAAAGAUUAUCAAUUUAAAAGUAUGAUCAAGUAUGCCUCAAAAACUAGAAACAUUUCAAAAUGUAGAACAAACGUUGAAAAAUUGUUUUGCCAGGAAAGAGUUCAAGUUCAGUUAAGGAUUUGAGAGGCUUUUAAACAAGGAUCAGUAGGAUAGUUAUCAUAUUUACUUAAUAUAUGUCUGAUAUUCAGUGCUGGUUCUUUUUCCUGUUUGUGCAACAAUGAAGUGUGUCAUGUGUGUUUUAUAGCCUCUAUCAUUAAUCACACCAGAGUCUCAUUUUAAAACAUUUUAAUGUUAAAACAUCCCCACACUUAUACACAGGUAAAAUUAGUUUUUUUUUUUUUAAAGUUGUAAUCUGUACUUUUUUUUUUUUGCAAUUUUUGAAACAGCUACAUUAAUCCCUAAAAAUCCCACCAUACUGAAAAUGUAUGGCGUGUAUUUUCUAUAGUAAGUAAUAUGAGGAAAACAUGAUUAGCUGUGCCAAAGAAAUUUUAUACAUUGUUUACAUGAUGAGGCCACAGUACUUACUGAGGACUUCAUAUGGUUUUUUUGUUUAUUAUUAUUGAGAAAAGAGCUGAGGUUACCACAUUCAUUCUUUGUGUUAGAAAUGUAGGAGUGUGGUGGUUUUCUGCAAUAUUUAGAGCUUAGUCUCAUAAUUUGGAAUUUAAGAUAAUAAGUAGUAACAAGGCAAGUCUUUUAUGUAAGACAGUCAAACAGUGUCACUUCAGGGACAAAGGCCUGGAAGCCCUUAAAAUAAGUUAUCUUAGAUGUGCCAGAACAUAUUCAGAGCUUUAUUCCUUUAAGCUUAAGGCUUCAAUACUUGUAGAAAUGCAAAUAUUCUUGAGAAAUGAUACAUUUUUUGUUCUCAAUUUCUCAAUUCUACAUACCUGAUUAUGAGUGAAGUAUCCAAAGCAGGUUUUCAUCAGCAUGGGGGAUGGAAGGUAGGUAUAAUAUGAGGACAAUGGAAACUUUGGGAGAAGGGAGUGAGGAAAUGGAUAAAGAGAAAUUUGAAAAUUUUAGGCUGGACUUGAGCACUAUUGCUGCUUUCCUAUGAACUAUCAGAAUGUUUAAAUGCUUUAUCAUUCAUGGUCCACUCUCAACCAACAUUUAUUAUCCUUUAGUAAUUAAACAAUGGUUUUACAUACAUUUUUAUAAUGUAGAAGGAAAUUCAAGAUUCCAUAAUCGUAAAAUUUUUCAGAUUUGUCUAAUGUGUAAUUUGUGCAUCUUCACAUGCUGCUAAAUGCAGAUUUAAACAUUACAUCUGAGGAUCAUGACUUUUCCUCCUUUCUUGGAGAUCUUGGUAUAAAAUUCAUCUGCUGUUAUAAAAUCAGGUUUCUACAGAGUUCGUUUCACACUAAAGGUAGUUUGUUACUGUUUGCAUGAGGAAACCAUGUAUGUCUCAAUCUUUAAUUUUAGGUGGUAGUGUUUAUUGUUCACCCUCCCUCUUGCCUCCAAAAGAAUGCUGAAUUAUACGCCAAUAUUUCCAUGUGUAUUCUGUUGCCUUGAUGCGUACUAUACUUGUUGCAUGUAUAUUAAAAAUUUUGUACUAUG